CUUGUGAUUCACUGCUAAGGAUCUUAAGCCCACCUUGGCCCUGACCUCGUUGGAAAACGAAGCUCCCCGCAGGGUCCCGGCCUCUAGGGCUGCUGUGCGGGCGGGGGUGGCCUGGAGCUAUUUCCAUUCGGCGGCGGGAACAGGUGCCGGCGCCUCCGCCCCAUCCCCAGGGGCCGCCUCCCCCGGGGCGGCCUCCAGGCUGCCGAGACCUAUAAAGGCGCCAGGUUUUCUCAAUGAAGCCGGGACGCACUCCGGAGCGCACUGCGUGGUCGCACCCUACCCGGGCUGCCUUGGAAGUCGUCCCCGCCGCCCCUCCGCACCGGCAUGAAGCUCAUCGUGGGCAUCGGAGGCAUGACCAACGGCGGCAAGACCACGCUGACCAACAGCCUGCUCAGAGCCCUGCCCAACUGCUGCGUGAUCCAUCAGGAUGACUUCUUCAAGGCUCCUCUGUUUCAGCCCCAAGACCAAAUAGCAGUUGGGGAAGACGGCUUCAAACAGUGGGACGUGCUGGAGUCUCUGGACAUGGAGGCCAUGCUGGACACCGUGCAGGCCUGGCUGAGCAGCCCGCAGAAGUUUGCCCGUGCCCACGGGGUCAGCGUCCAGCCAGAGGCCUCGGACACCCACAUCCUCCUCCUGGAAGGCUUCCUGCUCUACAGCUACAAGCCCCUGGUGGACUUGUACAGCCGCCGGUACUUCCUGACCGUCCCGUAUGAAGAGUGCAAGUGGAGGAGAAGUACCCGCAACUACACAGUCCCUGAUCCCCCCGGCCUCUUCGAUGGCCACGUGUGGCCCAUGUACCAGAAGUAUAGGCAGGAGAUGGAGGCCAACGGUGUGGAAGUGGUCUACCUGGACGGCAUGAAGUCCCGAGAGGAGCUCUUCCGUGAAGUCCUGGAAGACAUUCAGAACUCGCUGCUGAACCGCUCCCAGGAAUCAGCCCCCUCCCCGGCUCGCCCAGCCAGGACACAGGGACCCGGACGCGGAUGCGGCCACAGAACGGCCAGGCCUGCAGCGUCCCAGCAGGACAGCAUGUGAGCGUUUCCCUAUGGGGGUGUCUGUACGUAGGAGAGUGGAGGCCCCACUCCCAGUUGGGCGUCCCGGAGCUCAGGGACUGAGCCCCAAGACGCCUCUGUAACCUCGCUGCAGCUUCAGUAGUAAACUGGGUCCUGUUUUUUUAA